GAAUUCAACACAGACACACAUAUCCCUUCAAAAACUUUUAUUUGUAUCAACAGUUCCUAGCUCUUGACUUAGCUUAGAGCUUUUAAAAGAGCAGACACCUUAUAUAUUUGAGAUUGAAAAAGUUUCUGCUAUUAAUCAGAAAUAAUCAUUUCUAUUUUCUGGCUUACCCCUUGGAAUAAGCCAAAAAUAAAACCAAAGUUACAUUUCCUGACAGAUGGAUAAGAAAACAAUAGAAGGAACAUCCUGAAUUCUAGAGUUGACUCUUGCUGGUGAAGUACACCUUCAGCUUAGUCCAUUCUCCUAAGUAAAGCCUGAAGGAAAACUCUUAACACCUAAUUCUUUGUGGAAAAAUGAUCAACUAGCCAUUUCACAGGCUAUAGAACAAAAGUACAAUUGGGCAUCUUUCCUUAUGUCCUGGGAUCAGGGGUGCUUACAUUUAACAUUGAUCAGGUAAAGAGGAGAGGCUGUGCCUAAGGUCUGAGAAAAGGCUUGCUCUAAGCAAGCUGUGGUGAGGCACAGGAUGACUAGGGAAUGGCAGAGAACAGGCUGGCCUACUGUCAGUUCAAGCAACCAGCUGAGCAGCAGCAGUCUAAAAAGCCCCAAACAGAACACCUCCAUGGAUUCAGGGAAGGGCUGAGGCACUGCCUUUCUAGUAUGUGCCAAAAAAAACAUAACUCUGAAUUGGGGCCCAGGGGACUUUGAGUUUGUAUGGGGAGGGAAAAGGAGUGAGCAGUUCUCCUCCCCUCCCCACAGCCUUAGGCCAACACAAACUGCAAAUUGGUAAGCAGCACCUUAAUACCUCUUGUGACAGUUACGGCUGAAGUGGCAGGGUCAAGCUUGUAGGUGUUGGCAUCCCCCUUUUUAUAUCGGUCCCGGAAGACAUAGAUGCUCCCGUUACAGCUGGCAAUCUUCCAGAGGGAUGGGGCAGAGCUCCAGGCCUCAGGAAGGCAAAGCCGGGUGAAGCUGUCUAGCAAGGGAUUGUAGCACACCAGGGAGUCCCCUUCAGCCACGAUGAACACCAGAUCUUUAUGCACAGCUGCGUGCAUGCGGCCUGCAAAGGGCAGCACAUAGGGCUUCACAUGGCAUUUGUCUGUCUCUGUGUCAAAGCACUGGAUGAGUCGGGAAGGUUUGGUAAAGAAGUCCAGAUCAUUCUCCUCCCCCCCUAGUAAGUAGAUGAUCCCGUUGAGGUUGGCACCAGCAGCCCCUGACACAGCCACCUCUAGCUGAGUUGUCUCUGUCCACACAUUAUCACCUACGCGAUAAUAAAUGACUGCGUUGGAGAGGGUA